ACGGUGGCCGCGAAGCUAGGGCCACCAUGGCGGACCGCAGGCGGCGGCUCCGGCCGGGGACGUUGGCCCCGGUGCGCGAGGGCGUGAACUGCAGGUCCAGAUGUUUCACAAAGCACAAGAACGGGCUGAAGUUCCCCACCUCUCUGCACAGCCGGCAGUUGGUAUUUCCAAGAAAGGGGCUGGACGACUUCAGGAAGGGCUGCCCGCCUUGCACUGGUCUGGUGACUCAGGUCCCUGUGGAGGGCUUUCUGCCCCAGAUUUAUCACAGAGCUCCCCAACUGGCCCCAAAGAAGAGGCAGAUCAAGCUGCUCAAGGAAGCAGACGUGCUUUCCAAGCUCUCGCCAGCCCAGCAGGCUCGGAAGGCAUUCCUGGAGGACGUGGAGGCCCACCUGACCCCACAUCCCUUAGCGCUCUACCUGAAUCUGGAAGAAGCUAUGCCCAUAGAGCUCUUAUCAAAGGUGCUGGAAGUGCUUGAUCCUGACCGGAAGCUGGAGGACACAUGGGCUUAUUGUCAGGACACCAGGAAAGGAAUGAAGGAACCCACGAAGCUUUUAAAAAAACAUUCUACCCAAGUCUACCUGGGACCUUCCAAGAAGACGUCUGUGUCAAACGCAGGCCAAUGGCUUUAUGAAGAAAAGCCACAUAAAAUGGAUUUGCUCCAUGAAAAUGGUCCUCGUCCUGGUCUUCAUGAAAAUGGAAUUUCGGACAUCGAUGAAGAGUUCAUCUUGAAACAGUUUGACAUUGACUAUGAGACCAAACCAAGCCAUGAUGCGCUCCACACGAUGAAGCUAAAUCAGGUUCCUCUGGAGCUAAAGCGUAGUGUGGGGCUCAGUAAACUGCAGGAGACAGAGUUCUUCCAGAAACUAGGCUAUGAGAGGAAACUCCAGAAACCACAGAAUCCUUAUAAGCCAAAGUGGGUGAAGAUGAGGUAUGGAGCAUGGUAUUUGAACCCCAAGUUGUGGAAAAAGCAAAGAGUAGACGAGCCUCUGGUUGACCCUGAGGUCUCACAUAAGGCUCAAGAGGAGAAUUUUAAAAAGGAGCUGCAGGAACAGAGCAUCUUCAAGAAAGCAAUGGACAUUUGAUUUCUAAGACCAAAGACCUUGGUAAACUGCAAGCAGCAUCAUGGAGAUUGCAGAAUCCUUCCAGGGAAGUCUGUGACAAUUCAAGAGAACAUGUUCCUUCUGGACAGUUUCCAGACACAGAAGCUCCAGCUACCUCUGAGACCAGUAACUCUAGGAGUUACUCUGAAGUUUCAAGAAAUGAAAGCCUUGAAUCUCCUAUGGGAGAAUGGGGAUUCCAAAAAGGACAAGAGAUAUCUGCUAAAGCAGCUACAUGUUUUGCAGAGAAGUUGCCUUCUAGCAACCUGCUCAAGAACAGAGCUAAAGAAGAAAUGAGCCUCUCUGAUUUGAACAGUCAGGACCGGGUUGACCACGAGGAGUGGGAAAUGGUGCCUAGGCACUCAUCUUGGGGGGAUGUUGGUGUGGGUGGCAGUCUUAAGGCUCCAGUGUUAAACCUAAACCAGGGAAUGGACAAUGGAAGAAGCACUUUGGUGGAAGCAAGAGGUCAGCAAGUGCAUGGGAAAAUGGAAAGGGUAGCAGUGAUGCCUGCAGGGUCUCAGCAAGUUAGUGUCAGGUUCCAGGUCCAUUAUGUCACAAGCACUGAUGUGCAAUUCAUUGCAGUAACUGGAGACCAUGAGUGUCUUGGGAGAUGGAACACUUACAUCCCACUCCACUAUAACAAGGAUGGGUUCUGGUCUCAUUCCAUUUUCCUGCCUGCAGAUACAGUGGUGGAGUGGAAGUUUGUGUUGGUAGAGAAUGGGGGAGUUACCCGCUGGGAAGAAUGCAGCAAUAGAUUCCUAGAAACUGGCCAUGAGGAUAAAGUGGUUCACGCAUGGUGGGGGAUUCACUGAUUCAGUUUGCAAAGUAAUGGAGAAGCUGUAGAACAAUGUGGAAGAGGCUGAGGUUGUGGAACACACUGAAUAAAAUAAAGGCAGUGUGACUCCAAAUUCAGCCAUCUGAAUUGUUUAAAUUUGCUAGUGGAUUUUGUCUAAUGUGCAGAAAUAUAUAUGUCUAAUGUGCAGAAAUAUAUAUGUGUGUAUGUGUGUAUAUAUAUGCACACACACACAGAUAAUGCUUCCAGUGAAUGUGAACUUCUUUUCCCUGUGGCACUGAUUGACAGACUUGUGCUGAUCCAUUAUUACUUUAGGGCUUGAUUCUCUUGGGGAGUGACUUGGCUAAGCUUCAGGUGUAAACUGUGGUCACGGAGCAAAAACAUUAACCAGCUGCCCAGGGUUCAAGCUUGAGCCUUUAGGUGAUCUUUAAACUAUGGUAGUAAAAUAAGCCUCACUCAAACAUAGCUGACUUCCUAUUGGUACAGCUUGAAAAGCACUUUUUACUACAUACACAUUUUAUGCUUAAAAAGUUAACAUGAUACGAAACUGUGAUUAGAAAAUAUCUGGUCUGGAUGUGAUUAGUAAGGAUACAAGAUAAUGUUCUAAGACUGCCUAAUGCUUUUUGUUUGAUUUUCAUCUGCCAGGCGUUGUUAUGUGCUAUGAGGGUAGCAAGUACGUCUUUGUCUUAAUGAUCUAAGGCUGGUGUAGAAACAAAGGGCCUAAUGAGAACCAAUCAUCAUGGAAGUCAGUUGCGGGGGCAGCCCAUAAGGAAAGGGAAAGUGAGUGGGGUUGGGCAUAGGCUGAGUGAGGUGGCCUGAAUGACACCUCUUAGAGGACUGUGAAGUACAGGCACAGCCCGACUGCAGGGAGGGAUGCACCCAUCAUUUACCCAUGGGAGCAUCUGUAGGACCAUCUCUCUCCCACUUCUUCUCCCCUCCCCCACCGCAUCUGGCCAGAUGGACUGUCCUACAGCAAUCGUUUCCAUCUGUCACCCUCUUCCCUCUCCUUUCAUACCAGUCACUAUCUUGGGUAACAAAUUUAUACAGGACAGUGGUACAGAAAUACAUCUUUGCUCUGAGAAUACAGCAAAUAUUAACUUAAAUUAUUAUAACUGAACAAAUAAUAAAACCUGAAUUUUAAUAUCUUCA